AACGCGGAGGACCUCUGGGUGCCUGCAGGGGAGCUGCUCCAGCCGGGCCGCCGGGAGCGGUGGGGAGAGCAUCGCGGAGCCGCCCCUCCACGCGCCCGCCCAGCCGCGCUCGCCCACUGGGCUCUCCCGGCUGCAGUGCCAGGGCGCAGGACGCGGCCGAUCUCCCGCUCCCGCCACCUCCGCCACCAUGCUGCUCCCCCAGCUCUGCUGGCUGCCGCUGCUCGCUGGGCUGCUCCCGCCGGUGCCCGCUCAGAAGUUCUCGGCGCUCACGUUUUUGAGAGUGGAUCAAGAUAAAGACAAGGAUUGUAGCUUGGACUGUGCGGGUUCGCCCCAGAAACCUCUCUGCGCAUCUGACGGAAGGACCUUCCUUUCCCGUUGUGAAUUUCAACGUGCCAAGUGCAAAGAUCCCCAGCUAGAGAUUGCAUAUCGAGGAAACUGCAAAGACGUGUCCAGGUGUGUGGCCGAAAGGAAGUAUACCCAGGAGCAAGCCCGGAAGGAGUUUCAGCAAGUGUUCAUUCCUGAGUGCAAUGACGACGGCACCUACAGUCAGGUCCAGUGUCACAGCUACACGGGAUACUGCUGGUGCGUCACGCCCAACGGGAGGCCCAUCAGCGGCACUGCCGUGGCCCACAAGACGCCCCGGUGCCCGGGUUCCGUAAAUGAAAAGUUACCCCAACGCGAAGGCACAGGAAAAACAGAUGAUGCCGCAGCUCCAGCGUUGGAGACUCAGCCUCAAGGAGAUGAAGAAGAUAUUGCAUCACGUUACCCUACCCUUUGGACUGAACAGGUUAAAAGUCGGCAGAACAAAACCAAUAAGAAUUCAGUGUCAUCCUGUGACCAAGAGCACCAGUCUGCCCUGGAGGAAGCCAAGCAGCCCAAGAACGACAAUGUGGUGAUCCCUGAGUGUGCGCACGGCGGCCUCUACAAGCCAGUGCAGUGCCACCCCUCCACGGGGUACUGCUGGUGCGUCCUGGUGGACACGGGGCGCCCCAUUCCCGGCACAUCCACAAGGUACGAGCAGCCGAAAUGUGACAACACGGCCAGGGCCCACCCAGCCAAAGCCCGGGACCUGUACAAGGGCCGCCAGCUACAAGGUUGUCCGGGUGCCAAAAAGCAUGAGUUUCUGACCAGCGUUCUGGACGCGCUGUCCACGGACAUGGUCCACGCCGCCUCCGACCCCUCCUCCUCGUCAGGCAGGCUCUCAGAACCCGACCCCAGCCAUACCCUAGAGGAGCGGGUGGUGCACUGGUACUUCAAACUACUGGAUAAAAACUCCAGUGGAGACAUCGGCAAAAAGGAAAUCAAACCCUUCAAGAGGUUCCUUCGCAAAAAAUCAAAGCCCAAAAAAUGUGUGAAGAAGUUUGUUGAAUACUGUGACGUGAAUAAUGACAAAUCCAUCUCCGUACAAGAACUGAUGGGCUGCCUGGGCGUGGCGAAAGAGGACGGCAAAGCGGACACCAAGAAACGCCACACCCCCAGAGGUCAUGCUGAAAGUACGUCUAAUAGACAGGAUGCAAUGGUGGUGUCCUCCAGACCCAAAGCCACAACCCAUCGCAAGUCAAGAACACUUUCCAGAAGAUAAACAUGAGUGGGUUCAUGUCUCUCUCCUUCAAAGCCAGGACAAAAUCCCCACUUCUUUGCUGCCGCGAGUCAAUUUGUGAUUUAUUUUGUCUGCACCUGUUUGAUGCCAGGUCGACAUUUCCUAAGGCAAGCCCCUGUAUUUGUUGUGGAUUUAAGUGGAGGCGGCCAGCACACACCUUGGAUGUAAUUUAAAACCAUUUCCUGAGGAAAGAUGUGUGAUAUGCUUUCCUUUGUUUAGCAAAUGUUUAUGGUUUUAACUUUAAAUCUCACCGCAAAUCACUUACACUUGAAAACAGGGCUGGUCUGAAAGUAAUUACCCUCCCUGAGUGCCAAGACCUCCAGAAGUUGUUUUCAUUCCCGAAUGGCAAUCACUGUACUCAUGCGCUCCACGCAUCUUAAAUAAACUCAGUUCAAAGCACAUGCCUCCUGCUUCAGCUCUUUUUUCCAAAAAGAGAAACAGAAGCAGGUUCCCCCUCCUUUUAUAGUGCCUGCGUGGACACGCGGACCUCCAUGCCUUUCAUGCUGUGGCUAUGUCAGCAAACUACGAUAUUGGGAUGAUCCUAACGGGCAAGCCAGCUGCGGCUCCUACCGGCCGUGGCCAUUGAAGGCCACCAUGUUGCUUUGAAACAUCUCAAAGAAUAACAUAGUGCCAGCCAGCAAGGGUUUCACCAUAUGCAUGACCCAGACAGGAACUAUCAAAAGAAGGGAUCACGGGAAGGUGCAUGAUGCUAAUGUGGAAUCCAGAGGAGCUCUUUCCUGAUCUCUUCAGCUUCCGCUGCCACUCCAGAAUCAUCAGAGCUGAUAUUAAAUAAGUUAAAAUGUUAGUCCACCGUCUCCUCCUGCAAUCCUAACCAUCUUUUGAGACUGUUAGAAUACUUUGACGGGUUGUCUUUCUGUGCAACUAAUUUAAACCUCAAGUUUAGUGUAGGAGAUGGGUUUGUCUUCUCACCUCUUCAGAUCUUUAUCAAGGGGGAAUAAAAGCCAACCCAGAAACCUAAACUUUAAAAUUUAAUUAUUUGAAAUAAUAAAACAGAAGAAGGGAUCAACAUUUGUCGGAAUUGGCACUCUUGGAAAACUAAGUCUAGGAGAUCAUAUAUUGCUUUUUUUUUUUCAUUCUAAAUUACUUUUAAUUGAAAGUCAAGAUGCUGAGUUACAGUUGUUUAUCAUUAUAAUAAGCAAACUUUUUAAGUUGGAUUUCUUCUUAAAGAGGUAAACUAGUGAACAAAAAAGAUAAAAAGGAAAAUUAAGAAUCAACUAUGCCUUUAUCAAAUUUGAAGCAUAAGUUAUAUUAUUAAAAUUAUUUUUGUAUAAUCAAGGUGAUAAGACAUUCUGGAAAACAUUUAAUGUAUUUAGUACUUAGAAUAUUUACAGUGGAUGUUACUUUUUUGAAACGAUAUAUUUUUCCCAAUUUUUCUAUCAUGUCAAGGAAGGAAACUGUUAAGAAGUUACCAGUGUCCAAAAUGUCUUCAUUGUUUCUUACUCAUACUUACACCUCACAUGACCUGCCCAGCCCUCUUUGGUUCAGUUCAUUCCCAGAAGCCAAGCCUUAGUCUUCACAGAUGAGCGACACACACCUCUGAAUAUAAUGUCUCUUUUUUGUUUUUUCCUUUUCAGCCAAGGAAACAAGGAUAAAUGGCUCAUACCCCGAAGGCAGUUCCUAGACACAUGGGAAAUUUCCCUCACCAAAGAGCAAUUAAGAAAACAAAAACAGAAACACAUAGUAUUUGCACUUUGUACUUUAAAUGUAAAUUCACUUUGUAGAAAUGAGCUAUUUAAACAGACUGUUUUAAUCUGUGAAAAUGGAGAGCUGGCUUCAGAAAAUUAAUCACAUACAAUGUAUGUGUCCUCUUUUGACCUUGGAAAUCUGUAUGUGGUGGAGAAGUAUUUGAAUGCAUUUAGGCUUAAUUUCUUCGCCUUCCACAUGUUAACAGUAGAGCUCUAUGCACUCCGGCUGCAAUCGUAUGGCUUUCUCUAACCCCUGCAGUCACUUCCAGAUGCCUGUGCUUACAGCAUUGUGGAAUCAUGUUGGAAGCUCCACAUGUCCAUGGAAGUUUGUGAUGUACGGCCGACCCUACAGGCAGUUAACAUGCAUGGGCUGGUUUGUUUCUUGGGAUUUUCUGUUAGUUUGUCUUGUUUUGCUUUCCAGAGAUCUUGCUCAUACAAUGAAUCACGCAACCACUAAAGCUAUCCAGUUAAGUGCAGGUAGUUCCCCUGGAGGAAAUAAUAUUUUCAAACUGUCGUUGGUGUGAUACUUUGGCUCAAAGGAUCUUUGCUUUUCCAUUUUAAGCUUCUGUUUUGAGUUUUGCCCUGGGGCUUGAAUGAGUCCCAGAGAGUCGUUCGGAUGGUGGGAGGCUGCCUAGGAGGCAGUAAAUCCAGUCACAGUGCCUGGGAGGGGCCCAUCCUUCCAAAAUGUAAAUCCAGUCGCGGUGUGACCGAGCUGGCUAACAGGCUUGUCUGCCUGGUUUUCCUCCUACACGUGGACAUUAUUCUCCUGAUCCUCCUACCUGGUCCACCCCAGGGCUACCGGAAGGUAAAAUCUUCACCUGAACCAAUUAUGAGCAGUCUCCUUACUGAAGGUACAGCCGGAUACGUGGUGCCCCCGGGGCUGGUGUUGGCAGCCGGGGGGAGGUGCCUGAGGGUCCCCACGGUUCCUUUCUGCUUUUCUGAAUGCAUCAAGGGUACGAGAACUUGCCAAUGGGAAAUUCAUCCGAGUGGCACUGGCAGAGAAGGAUAGGAGUGGAAUGCCCACACAGUGACCAACAGAACUGGUCUGCGUGCAUAACCAGCUGCCACCCUCAGGCCUGGGCCCCAGAGCUCAGGGCACCCAGUGUCUUAAGGAACCAUUUGGAGGACAGUCUGAGAGCAGGAACUUCAAGCUGUGAUUCUAUCUCGGCUCAGACUUUUGGUUGGAAAAAGAUCUUCAUGGCCCCAAAUCCCCUGAGACAUGCCUUGUAGAAUGAUUUUGUGAUGUUGUGAUGCUUGUGGAGCAUCGCGUAAGGCUUCUUGCUUAUUUAAACUGUGCAAGGUAAAAAUCAAGCCUUUGGAGCCACAGAACCAGCUCAAGUACAUGCCAAUGUUGUUUAAGAAACAGUUAUGAUCCUAAACUUUUUGGAUAAUCUUUUAUAUUUCUGACCUUUGAAUUUAAUCAUUGUUCUUAGAUUAAAAUAAAAUAUGCUAUUGAAACUA